AUUGAGCCAGCGAGGAGUGAAGCUGAGCCUGGCCUCACACGCUCCUAGAGGACCACCUCCUGAGAGAGUUCUUUCACCCCCUCUUCUUUCUCCAAGCUCCCCUCCUGCUCUCCCUCCCUGCCCAAUACAAUGCAUUCUUGAGUGGCAGCGUCUGGACUCCAGGCAGCCCCAGAGAACCGAAGCAAGCCAAAGAGAGGACUGGAGCCAAGAUACUGGUGGGGGAGAUUGGAUGCCUGGCUUUCUUUGAGGACAUCUUUGGAGCGAGGGUGGCUUUGGGGUGGGGGCUUGUGCUGCAGGGAAUACAGCCAGGCCCCAAGAUGGACACUUCUGGGCACUUCCAUGACUCGGGGGUGGGGGACUUGGAUGAAGACCCCAAGUGCCCCUGUCCAUCCUCUGGGGAUGAGCAGCAGCAGCAGCAGCAGCAGCAACAGCAGCAGCAGCCACCACCGCCAGCGCCACCAGCAGCCCCCCAGCAGCCCCUGGGACCCUCGCUGCAGCCUCAGCCUCCGCAGCUUCAGCAGCAGCAGCAGCAGCAGCAGCAGCAGCAGCAGCAGCAGCCACCGCAUCCCCUGUCUCAGCUCGCCCAACUCCAGAGCCAGCCCGUCCACCCUGGCCUGCUGCACUCCUCUCCCACCGCUUUCAGGGCCCCCCCUUCGUCCAACUCCACCGCCAUCCUCCACCCUUCCUCCAGGCAAGGCAGCCAGCUCAAUCUCAAUGACCACUUGCUUGGCCACUCUCCAAGUUCCACAGCUACAAGUGGGCCUGGCGGAGGCAGCCGGCACCGACAGGCCAGCCCCCUGGUGCACCGGCGGGACAGCAACCCCUUCACGGAGAUCGCCAUGAGCUCCUGCAAGUAUAGCGGUGGGGUCAUGAAGCCCCUCAGCCGCCUCAGCGCCUCCCGGAGGAACCUCAUCGAGGCCGAGACUGAGGGCCAACCCCUCCAGCUUUUCAGCCCUAGCAACCCCCCGGAGAUCGUCAUCUCCUCCCGGGAGGACAACCAUGCCCACCAGACCCUGCUCCAUCACCCUAAUGCCACCCACAACCACCAGCAUGCCGGCACCACCGCCAGCAGCACCACCUUCCCCAAAGCCAACAAGCGGAAAAACCAAAACAUUGGCUAUAAGCUGGGACACAGGAGGGCCCUGUUUGAAAAGAGAAAGCGACUGAGUGACUAUGCUCUGAUUUUUGGGAUGUUUGGAAUUGUUGUUAUGGUGAUAGAGACCGAGCUCUCUUGGGGUUUGUACUCAAAGGACUCCAUGUUUUCGUUGGCCCUGAAAUGCCUUAUCAGUCUGUCCACCAUCAUCCUUUUGGGCUUGAUCAUCGCCUACCACACACGUGAAGUCCAGCUCUUCGUGAUCGACAAUGGCGCGGAUGACUGGCGGAUAGCCAUGACCUACGAGCGCAUCCUGUACAUCAGCCUGGAGAUGCUGGUGUGCGCCAUCCACCCCAUUCCUGGCGAGUACAAGUUCUUCUGGACGGCACGCCUGGCCUUCUCCUACACACCCUCCCGGGCGGAGGCCGAUGUGGACAUCAUCCUGUCUAUCCCCAUGUUCCUGCGCCUGUACCUGAUCGCCCGAGUCAUGCUGCUGCACAGCAAGCUCUUCACCGAUGCCUCGUCCCGCAGCAUCGGGGCCCUCAACAAGAUCAACUUCAACACCCGCUUUGUCAUGAAGACGCUCAUGACCAUCUGCCCUGGCACUGUGCUGCUCGUGUUCAGCAUCUCUCUGUGGAUCAUUGCUGCCUGGACCGUCCGUGUCUGUGAAAGUCCUGAAUCACCAGCCCAGCCUUCUGGCUCAUCACUUCCUGCUUGGUACCAUGACCAGCAGGACGUAACUAGUAACUUUCUGGGUGCCAUGUGGCUCAUCUCCAUCACAUUCCUUUCCAUUGGUUAUGGGGACAUGGUGCCCCACACAUACUGUGGGAAAGGUGUCUGUCUCCUCACUGGCAUCAUGGGUGCAGGCUGCACUGCCCUUGUGGUGGCCGUGGUGGCCCGAAAGCUGGAACUCACCAAAGCGGAGAAGCACGUUCAUAACUUCAUGAUGGACACUCAGCUCACCAAGCGGAUCAAGAAUGCUGCAGCCAAUGUCCUUCGGGAAACAUGGUUAAUCUAUAAACACACAAAGCUGCUAAAGAAGAUUGACCAUGCCAAAGUGAGGAAACACCAGAGGAAGUUCCUCCAAGCUAUCCACCAGUUGAGGAGCGUCAAGAUGGAACAGAGGAAGCUGAGUGACCAAGCCAACACUCUGGUGGACCUUUCCAAGAUGCAGAAUGUCAUGUAUGACUUAAUCACAGAACUCAAUGACCGGAGCGAAGACCUGGAGAAGCAGAUUGGCAGCCUGGAGUCGAAGCUGGAGCAUCUCACCGCCAGCUUCAACUCCCUGCCGCUGCUCAUCGCCGACACCCUGCGCCAGCAGCAGCAGCAGCUCCUGUCUGCCAUCAUCGAGGCCCGGGGUGUCAGCGUGGCAGUGGGCACCACCCACACCCCAAUCUCCGAUAGCCCCAUUGGGGUCAGCUCCACCUCCUUCCCGACCCCGUACACAAGUUCAAGCAGUUGCUAAAUAAAUCUCCCCACUCCAGAAGCAUUACCCAUAGGUCUUAAGAUGCAAAUCAACUCUCUCCUGGUCGCUUUGCCAUCAAGAAACAUUCAGACCAGGGAACGGAAAGAAGAGAGACCGAGCUAAUUAACUAACUCAUGUUCAUUCAGCGUGCUUGGUCCGACAUGCCUUGAAACCAGAAAUCUAAUCUCUGUUUAGGUGCCUCUACUUGGGAGCGGGAAGAGGAGAUGACAGGAAGCGACGCCUCUGGCAGGGCCCUUGCUGCAGAGUUGGUGGAGAACAGAAAUCCACGCUCAAUCUCAGGUCUUCACGCGGGGGGUGGGGGUCAGAUGCACUGAAGUAGCCAACAGCGAAGCCAGUCCAGAAGAGGGGUCCGCUGGGAGGGAGGGUUGUGUCAGGCUUGGGGGAUGGGCUCUUCGCCAUGGGGGUCUUUGAACACACCUCUCUCCUUUCCUUUUGUCUACGGAAGCCUCUGGGUGACAAAAGUAAAAGAGAGCUGCCCACAACUUGCCAAAACAGAUAUACUCGAAUCAGACUGAAAAAAAAAAAAAAAGACACAGACAAAUAAAAAGCCAGAUUUUCCACUCGAUAUUAAUACCCACAUAAACCUGUGUGUUUGCAAACGUGUACAUGUACACACAUACACAUCCCACGUUCGCUUCAGGUCCUUUCUUAUUUGAGCUUAAUCCAAAUAAAAAGGGACUUGACACCUUACCCUGCAUACAAUAGGCACCCCUUACAUGUGUUUUGAGUUGGUCUGAAUCUGAACAUGGGGUGCUUUCAGUUCAGGUAGUUAGCUAGUUCUGGCCACAUUCUGAGUUUCACUGAAGAUGUGGAUCCCUUCAGACAUAAUGCACAUUGCUUUGUCCUGGAUAUGCACCUUGCUUGAUUUGAAAUGGAUGCCAAGCCAAAAUUGUUGGCAUUCAGGAGGGAUAAGCAGGCUUCUAAAAAUAACAGCAUCUGCAGAGUUUUCUUCUUCCAUCCAAACAAGUUGUGUUUCGAUGGUCCACAUGACCAGGUGUAUGUCUGUAAGUGUGGAGGGAGAGGACAAGAAAUUGUGCAUGUGUGUGCAGACAUGCACAAACAGGAGCAAUCCAAUAACACCUUAGUGAAUAGAAAUAUGGUUGGGGAUUUGCUGAGCUGUAUUUAUCCAGCAACAGGUUUCCAGCCCCAGAUGUUAGUAGUGCAAAAGGGCCAAGUGCCUCAAUUGUGAGCCUCUGAGCUAGGAGGAGAAGUGAUGAAGAGUGGCCUAUGUGGUCCCUUCUACCUGACCUUAAGUCAUCUCAAAAUGAAAUAUUGUGAGAAUGAAGGGAACCCUUAGGGAACCUUGUGGGUAAGGUAAGUGGACAUGGAUUUGUCAGUAGCCUGUUCCUACUGUGCCAUGUUAAUCUUGGUGCGAAAAACUAUUCCAAUACAUCUCAAACUCCAAGAGACUUCAGAAACAUCAAGAUUUAGUGUAAUGAGCGGCGCAGAAAAAUGUUUUCAUUGCUCCAUAAUCUGACCACACGUAACAUUUGUGACGUGAAAACCAUGACUUUCUCAUUCUGAGGUCUUUGGUUUCUGCCUGUGGGAAAUUGAAUGGCACUGUAUGGACUAUUUCAUCUGUUGAUGGUAAAACAAAAGGGUGAUUUUUUUGCUUGUGGUUGUCAUCUUGGGUUUACCUUUGUAAGAAGACAUCAUCACCAUUCUGAAGGCAGUGGCUUGGCAUGGAGAUUUUUAUUCUGUAGCACUGGGCCUGUUCUUCUAAGGACAGCACAAGGUAGACAAUUGUAGAGCCAAGGCCACUUUUUCAGGAAGAUCUAGUCUCUUGCUAACCCUCUUCUUUCUCUCUUGCUAUUGCUGCUGCUCUUUUGAUGGUUUAUAGUCUUAAUGGCCUGCCUUGAUAAUUCCUUUGAACACUUUCAUUAGUUGUUUUGCAUACCAGAGAUGCCGCACCUGCUGUUGGCUUAUUUUUUUACUUGUUCUAUUAACUGUUGAUUAUCUGAAUGUUUCCCCUCCUCCUUGUUUCAUGUCCCAAGAAUGGUGCUCCUGUUUUCAGUGACAGUUCAGCUGAACAUAUAAGCAGAUGUGUAAACAGAUGAAGUAACCAUGCAGUUUCCUUGUGGCAUUAGUUCCAUUUCACAAAGUGAAGACCACUGGUGGGCUGAUCUGAGUGUGCCAAUCCUGAUCAUUUAAACCUACAGCCUUCAACUGGUGAUUCCUACCCACCGUUUUCAUUCUGCUAUAACCCUGUGAUAUGUGUGCGUGUGGGUGUGAGUGUGGGUGUGUGCACAUAUAGAGAUUUAGUCUUAAUUUCAACCAAAUGACAUGCAAGAUUCCACUGCCACUCUUCCUGGCCAAAAGUGUGCACAGACUGUGAUUUAUUCAUUGUGGUCUGUGACUUUAACCCAUCAUUGAUGCUCUCACUUAGGUAAACCCUAAAGACCAAACUAGCAACACUAGUCAAGGGAGUGACUGGAGUUAUUUCUGGUAGCAGUAGCCACUGGCAUCCUAGAAACACAUGGACAUUUGUAGCAUGAAUUGACCUAUUGGUAGUGCAAUAGCUAUACAUGAUUUUUAUUCUUGGCAAAAGAAAAUGCUUCAAAAAAAAAGUGAUCAAACCUGCACAUUGAUCCUGUAAUAGCAAAUGGAAGGCUAUUUCUCUGUACUAGCAUUUCAGCUUUAUGUGGGAAAGUUACCCGUUCUCCUGCAAGUACAAUCAACCCUUGAUGACUUAAGUAUUAAUUAUUCUGGGUGUAGCUCACCCAAGUUUUCUUCCUACAUCUUUUGGCUAAUUCCACCACACCUCAGCAUCACAGUCAGAUGGGAAAAGGGGCAGGUGGAUUCUCAUGUCAUGCCUUCUUGUACCUUAUUUUCAAGUUUUGUGGUGGAGGAGGUUUAAUUAUCUGCUCAAGAAUCUGGUAUAUAUAGCCAGGUGCGGUGGCUCAUGCCUGUAAUCCCAGGACUUUGGGCAAGGCGAGAGGAUCACCUGAGGUCAGGAGUUCAAGACCAGCCUGGCCAACAUGGCAAAACCCCAUCUCUACUAAAAAUACAAAAAUUAGCUGGGUUUGGUGGUGGACACCUGUAGUCCCAGCUACUUGGGAGGCUGCGGCAGGAGAAUCACUUGAACCCCGGAAGUGGAGGUUGCAGUGAGCCAAGAUCGUGCCAUUGCACUCCAGCUUGGGUGACCGAGCAAGACUCCGUCUCAAAAAAAAAAAAAAAAUCGGCUAUAUGUAAAAACUAUUAAUUAUGUAACCUCACUCCAAUACUGUACUGAUCAAGAUCUGCCCACUCCUAGAGGACUGACCCAAUGGCAGAUCCCCUACUAUAAUCUUUCUGACAACUCAGUGACAGGUAAAAUCACUCUAAUAUUCCUAAAAUAUCUAGACACUUGAAUUAGAAAUACAGAACCACCCCCACCCCUGCCAUUGCUUAAGCCAUAUUAAAGCUUCAUGUACUGUAAAGUCAGGGAUGUACUGUGAUACUUUAAGACCACUAAUCUCAGUGGAAUUUCAGGACAUAGCAUUAGUUGGUAAAUUACACCAGACUAGGGGCUCACUCCUCCUUAGAUUGAAGUCCAAAUAAAAGUCUUCACCUUUGGAUCAAAGGCCACAUAUAUAUGAUCAUCAUCAAUAAAUUGUCAUAAAGUGUCUAUGAACUGCUCUUGCCAUCUUCCUAAUACGUAACUUCAUGACAUCAUGUCUCUAGAAGUGCUUAAUACAAUCCAAAAGAACAAGGGGGGAAGGCCCCAAGUCACCACUGACCGACCUCAGCAGGGGCCAGUGGUAGAACAACAAUCUUGUGAAUUAGGAGACAUAGAAAAUGUACGCAAAAGUAAAUUCCAAGCGCUGAGCAUGUACAAGCUAUUUUUAUUAUUAAAAGCCAAGAAGGAAGAGCAUUGAAGAAGUAAUGAUUUUAAUAUAGUGGGGGAUUUCCCCCUUAAAUUUUUAUAAUUUCCUUGUGAAUAAACAAUCAUGGAAAAGAAGAAACCUAGUCAUACAAAAUCAGAAUAAAUAAAAAUCUUAAGACUGGAUCCACAUCUUUGGCCAAUUCAUAUAAGCACCUAAUACAUCAAUUUCUCUGUACUUAAAAUGAAGAGAAUAAUUAAUAUUCUUAAGUACAAUGUUUUCAAUAGAGAACAAAUGAAAUCACCUUUGUCAUCAACAGCAGCCCAGACUGACUGUAUCUAGAUCACACCUUGAUGUUACGUUUGAAUGCAGUCAGUAGUUACCAAAAAGUAAUUAGUGCACAUUAAAUAGUGGUAAAAUCAGCAGGGAGAAAUAUGGGAUUAGCACGUAGUUCCAGAACCUUCCUCCUCCUCCAGAGUGCAACUCAACAAACAGUACACUCCAAAUUAAGAAUCAAUGUUUCAUCCCAGGACAAACGGUGUUGCUCCCAUCACAGUACCACAACUGAGAUACUGUGAAGUCAUUGCACUACCAGUAGGUUACUACUCUUUUGAAGUUACUGUUUUUAAAUCCUAAAAUAUGUCCCCAGUUUUCUACAUUCAUUCUUCUUCCCCUAAGAGUUGCUAGAAGCAGAUGAAGGAUCCCUAUUGACUCUGCAGGGUUUGAUUUCAGUACCUUAGACAGCUAUCUGGUGACUUCCCAGUAGGCACGAACAACCCCUUCUCUCCCCUUGCAGUCGGUGGGCUUGAUGACGCCCCAGACAGUAUCCUUUCCUUCUCUACUGCCGCCAAAAUAAACAUUAGGGAAAUGGGAUCAUUAACACCACUGAGAAAGGAGUUUACAGGGAUCGCAAUAGUAACUGUCUGCUUGUGGUAGUAGAAAGCUUGUGCCAGGCUGCAUGAAUAGAAAUUAAUGUUAAACUCCUGUUAGACGAGUAAUAUGUAGAUUUUUAUUGAAACAGACCACAGCUUAUUAAAAAGUACUCAGUGCAAUGGUAUAUACAUAUAUACAGAUAGAAAAAAAUAUAACUGUGAUCUUUUUGUCUUACGCCAUUACUGGAAACACCCAAACGUGAACUGGAGUUCCCUCUGAACAAAACCAUUGUCAAAUCUUCAACAUAUGACCUCCAAAUCUAGGUGCCAAGUGCCCUGUGACAGUUGUUUACACACCUGAAAAAUGUAUCCUGGAAGCUGUAAUCUUGGGCCUGGGCUAUGUGUUGAAACAAGCAAAAGAGACACAUCGUGACCAACCAAGCUGGUGGAGGAAAAGCACAAAAUUCAACUCCAACCUGCAGUUAGGAUCCCAAAGAGAUGUUGACAUUUAUAGCCAAAAAGAAAAAGUACAUAUAUAUAUAUAUAUAUAUAUAUAUAUAUAUAUAUAUAUAUAUAUAUCUGAAUCAGAUCGAAGCAGCCAACGUCCAGCUUCACUCAAGAAGGACAAGGAAUAAACAACAUUCUCUAGCUGUGUCAUGUUGUCUCAGUUUUUGAAUCUCAACCAGGACUGAUCCACCUUCAUCAGAUACGUUUUUUAAUGGCGCAACAACUCAAUUUUGGUCCCAGACUCUCCAUUCUGCACUGGCCACGAGAACAACAAGAGAAUGACAGGAUGUUAAUGGAGGAAACAUUUUCAUGGCAAGCUCAGAAACUGAAGUGUUUAUAUUCAGAAUCAGAUGAGCUUUAAUAUGAAUUUGCAUCUUGCCUCUGUACUGCUUGCUAUUUUUUAAUGAUAGGAGAAAGCAUAACAGUUUAUUUUAAAUAUGAAAUAUAUUGAUAUAUUAUAAAAUAUAUUGUAACUUUCAAUUAACAUUUUGUAUCAAACUAGUGUUUAGCAGGUCCACUGUCAGCCUGCUCUCCCAAUGACUGUUUCUGAGUACACAUCACUGUUAGUGAUUGCCGGGCACCCAGAAAAAGGGUCCUCCUACCACAGCCUACUGAACUGCCAUAUUCUAAUUCUCCAAGGCCUGGGUAUUAGAGACAAAAGAACAUUAUUCCAAGAGUAGAGGAAUAAUUCUACCCUAAAUUCUAUCAAGCCAUUUCAGAAGAGAUUUUAAAAGCCAUCACUCCUUUAGUAGCUCUGCAAAGCCAGUUUAAUAAAAGUUCAGGCUCUUUCUAUAUAAAUUCAAAGGCCUCAUUACAUAAAUUAUAUAAGUCUCAAACCUAGCCAACCAGUUUUCCUUUGACAAUGUCAGAAUUGGACAUAAGAAAGAGUCCUGUUUUCCUGUAACUUAAAAUACUCAAAAUCCUAGGCAUUCUGAGUUUCUCCAUGUACGUGAAACCGGGGUCGGCUUUCCAAACUACACAAGGCCCAACAAGAGUCCAGUGUGCAGAUGUGCUUUUCUAAAUUGGCAAUACCCUUGAGGGAGCAAGGUUCCCACAUGUUUAUCAAGGACAUGGAGCCCAGCUCCUAAGGGAGUGAUGGGAGGAGCCGGCAGGACAUGAACAGCCAGAGCCAGCAAAGAGCCGGGCUGCCUUUUCUGCUAGCUUCCUCUAGCUGGGAGGAAAUAAAGGGUUCCCGUUGAGAUAUUGUCCUUUAUAGCAAAAUUAAGCAACUCAUGGAAUCUACACCCCUCUUUCUCUACAGAGCAGCUGAGACAUACAUGUAGAAGUUCUCAGUUCCCUCCUUCAUAUGGCUAAGGCACUACUUCUAGAUGAAAACAGGAUGUGUUCGGUUACAGAAUAAAGAUUUUCUAGAAUCAGUGAGCCUCUUCUCACCUGGGACCCUCACUUGCUGUUGUUGCUUUGGUGCAAUAUUGUACAGGUGCAAACCAGGUUGCAUCGGGGCAGAUUAACUGAGCCUAUGUGUCUCUUCCCUUCCCAAGCCCUGAAAAUUCACAUAGAUUUACAGAUAGUGCAAAACAACAAGUUUUCUCCUGGGAAAAGGCUGGAAUCCUUCAAAUUUCAAUUUAUAUGAGCUUAAAGGUAUAUAAGUCAUGGGGCUCACUGACAUUAGGUAUUCAUGCUGUUUGAAAGAGAAAUGUCUAAAUGCCCGUUUUCAGUCUGUUUGUGUAGCUGAGCCCUAACUUGUACACAAGUUUUCUUGUUAUGGAGCUAAAUUCUCUCAGUGCCUGUAUUACUCCUCAGUUAUAUGUUAGGCCGAGCUCCACUAAAGCCAUCUGAACUCCAGGGCACUUGUUUUUAUCAGGUUACUUACUCACCGGAUAAUGGAAAUUGGCUUAUUUUCAAUUUUACAAUUGACUGAUGAAUGUAUUGGUGGUAAUUGAUUUAUUUCUUCACUUUUUUUUGCUACUAAAUGAUUUUUUCUUUUUUAAAAUUAUUAUUAUUAUUAUUUUGAGAUGGAGUCUCACUCUGUCGCCCAGGCUGGAGUGCAGUGGCGCCAUCUCAGCUCACUGCAAGCUCUGCCUCCUGGGUUCAUGCAAUUCUCCUGCCUCAGCCUCCCGAGUAGCUGGGAUUACAGGUGCGUGCCACCACGACCAGCUAAUUUUUUUGUAUUUUUAGUAGAGACAGGGUUUCAUCAUGUUAACCAGGAUGGUCUCGAUCUCCUGACCUCGUGAUCCACCUGCCUGGGCCUCCCAAAGUGAGCCACUGUGCCUGGCCCAGUAAGUGCUUUUUUCUUUUGGUUUUUCCUUCUAACACUGCUCAGACCAAGACUUACAUUUAUAAAGAGCAAAUAUAUUCUGACCUUUCCCCUCAAAGUUGUAUUCCAUCUAGAAUCAAGGAAACAAAUGCAAAUUCAUCAUUUGGGGAAAGCAGACCUCUUGACAGUAAUUCAAGUCCAUGGCUAUAUGCUAACCCUUGCUACUCAAAGUGUGGUCCACAGACCAGCAGCGUUAGCAUCAUCUGUAAGCUUGUUAGAAAUGCAGAAUCUCAGGCCCCACAUCAAACCUUCUUCAUCAGAAUUGGCCUUUUAACAAAUCCCCAGGUGACCUGUAUGCACCAGAAAUAUUGAUAAGCACUGGCCUCACCUCACCGUAGUGAUAACUAACCUCGUUAAUAAUUAGAGAAUGAAGCUAUCUCUUCCUUGAGUCUCAUUUACAGAAUUAUUUGAAGAUGUGAAGGUCCUGAAUGAUCAUAAGGAUUAAAAAAAUGCAUCUUUAAAUUCCACUUGAGGUUAUAUAACUUGGAUGGUCUACAUCAAACAUAAUAAAGUCAAUAAGAGAUAGUCUUUUUCCGGUCUUACCUAAAUAGCACUCCAUAUCCUUGAGCCACCUCAAAGCCCCCAUUUUUAAGUUUUAGUCUUUUUUUUUUUAGACCAGACUAGCAAAGCCAUCAGAAUAUCAGGUGGAACCUCAGGGCAGGUCCUCUGGAAGGCUACAGGAGUCUCUGCUUAGCAUAGUACAGAAAUUGUUGUGUUUCUCGAUCCUUGUGUUCUUCCCUUGAGGAACUCAGCAUCUCACCAGUAAGAACUCCCCUCCCCUAGAGGAAAAUAGCAAGAGAAGUUAGUUUAACCAUCUAGAAACAUUGCUAAUCUCCUUGAAAGCCAAUUCUCUUACUCAUUGCACCAACAAGAAACACUCCAAGGUGGGCAAGGAAAGACGUGAAUUCUGAUAUUGGCGCCAUAACUCGAUAUGUACCCAGAAACAGUUAUGUUCUAAAUUAAUGGCUUUAACCUGUUCAUUGUAAAAAGUGCCUUGGACUUCAAUCUAAAGAGGUCAGUAUAAAUAUGUAUGUGUGUGUGUGACGUGUAUGUAGGCAAAUAUUUACAGAUUUAUACAUACAUAGGUGCACACACAUAUACCCGCACAUUCAUAUAUAAUAUAUACAUACAUAUAUAAAUGCUUCAUAAUAUAUCAUAUUGCUAUUCACAGCUCCAUUUCUUUUGUCUGGUCCUAUGUUUAUUUGUUUAGUGAGACCUUUACAUAGAGAGGUUCUAUUCGGAACAUUGAUGUAUUUUUUGUUUGUUUUUUACUUUUUAUUAAAAAGGUAAAGGAUAUUAAAAAAAAAAAAAAAAGUCAAGUGCCUGAAGGUUUUGAAUGGAGUUACGGUAAACUUUCUCAGGUCACCAAAGAGGAAACAUUUUUCCUUUGGAAAACAUUUUUCUGUUUCAGUGACUUUGUUUUCCCUUGGUGGUAAUGCAUAAAUAAGAGUGGUUAAAGUGAUUUUGUAAGUUUUAUUUCAAUCCAUUUCUGUGGUUCCCAUAAGGCAAUAGCUAAAAAUUUGUUCAGUCUAGUGCCCAGUUUUCUCCACACAUCAGCAUCAGAAGGGCCCGGUCUUCACAUGCUCUGUGUGGUUUUGUUCGCGUUGUUACUGUGUUCCUUACUAAGGAAAGGCAAAUGAAAUUGCAGGGGCUGGAGCUUAGACCAGCUCCAAAUAUGGCUUCCUUUUGGUAACACACACAGAAGGUGGACUAGUGGGAAGUCUCUCUCCCUGAAGCAGGUGGGAACCUGUGUCUUAGAAGGCAGAGGAGUCCCAGUGAACUCUCCACAGCUCCAUGGGCCCUGCCUGUCUACAGUUAUACAACUGCCUGUAUGAGUCAGCCUUUCUCUACCUUAGCCAAAGGUCUUCUCUUUCUGUGGUGUGACAGCUUGUAAUGAACCAACUUGCUCUGGUUAGAAGUCCCUAGAGCUCCAGGAAGAGUCGCCAGGUUUCCAUUGCUGUGCUCAAAGCUCAAGGACACAUUAUACUUCUUUAAACCAACUAAAUCUCUCUAGCUCCCUGCCCCCAUGGUGACACUUUCAUAAUAGGCAGGGCCAAGUCAGAGAGGUCAUGCCCUGUAUACAGUGUCAAUCAGAAGAGACACUGCAAAAUGUCAGAGGUGACCAGAAAGACAACAGAUCUCUCCAGCUGUCCUCACAGCUGCAGGCACAUUUGUGGAAUUGUGAGUAGGAAGGCUUGGCAGCCAGGGGAUGGGAAAUGAAUUUCCCCAAGUUGAAAACCCUGUACCCUUACUUUCCUUCCCAUAAAUUUUUCUGUAGUUCUAGGUAAAUAAUAAUAAUAAUAAAAAUGCAAAUUAGGUGCUUUAGAAGGAGUAUGUAAUAUCUGGGACUUUUUCUAAGUUGGUAGACCUAAAAAAUGUUUUCAAAAAUAUAUCUAGCUGCAUUUCUACUGCUGUCAUUCCUUAAAGCUCUUCCUCCAAAAACUCCAUAUGAAUGAAUACAUUUACCAACUCAGUGAUUACUAAAUAAUAGUACUUUAUACUUAUACACAGUAAUACCUUUCAUCUAAGGAUCUCAAAUGCCAAUAUAUUAGUCAUCACCCUGUAAGGUGGAUGACAUAUUAUUCCCAUUAUUCCAAUGGGAAAAUUGGGCCAUAGAAAACUGAGGAGCAAAUGACUCAUCUACAGGAAUUAAAUGGAAAAAACAGGCUAGGAUUUCUCAGCACACUUUAGGAGUGAAUGAAAACUUACAGGCUUCAGUUCUACUGCUGGCCACCAUUGGAUUUGUAAGAUCCAGGAUGUGUAUUGACCACAUGUGUCCAGACCCAGGCUUAGGGCAUCUGGAAUGAGAGUGGUGGGCUGGUGUGUGGGUCUGAGGAUCUGGAUGGGAGACUGCAUUUUCUUCUCUGUGCAAAAUAUGGAAGUGUGACCUUGAAGGUGGGCUUAGUCUAUGGCCUUCCCCACUCCUGCUUGAACUGAAGCUGGAGAGAAUGGGCAUUUUUAAAUGUUACGGCAUAUGCUAAUAUAAUAUUAUGGCAUUAAAUAAAAACAAGAAGAGAACUGACUAAAACCAAAAAACCAAAAA